GGAGCCGCUGAGAAAGCGCAGAGAAGGCGGGCCCCGUCUGAGGUCUGGCAGUCAGAGACAGCCGGGCGCCCACGGCCCGAGCGCCCACGGCAGCACCAUGCCCGCACUCCUGGAGCGCCCCAAGCUUUCCAACGCCAUGGCCAGGGCGCUGCACCGGCACAUUAUGAUGGAGCGGGAGCGCAAGCGGCAGGAGGAAGAAGAGGUGGAUAAGAUGAUGGAACAGAAGAUGAAGGAAGAACAGGAGAGAAGGAAGAAAAAGGAGAUGGAAGAGAGAAUGUCAUUAGAGGAGACCAAGGAACAAAUUCUGAAGUUGGAGGAGAAGCUUUUGGCUCUACAGGAAGAGAAGCACCAGCUUUUCCUGCAGCUCAAGAAAGUUUUACAUGAGGAAGAAAAACGGAGGCGAAAGGAACAGAGUGACCUGACCACCCUAACAUCAGCUGCAUACCAGCAGAGCCUGACUGUUCACACAGGAACUCAUCUCCUCAGCAUGCAGGGGAGCCCUGGAGGACACAAUCGCCCAGGCACCCUCAUGGCAGCUGACAGAGCCAAACAAAUGUUUGGACCCCAAGUGCUUACGACCCGGCACUACGUGGGCUCAGCAGCUGCUUUUGCAGGGACACCAGAGCAUGGACAAUUCCAAGGCAGUCCUGGUGGUGCCUAUGGGACUGCUCAGCCCCCACCUCACUAUGGGCCCACACAGCCAGCUUAUAGUCCUAGUCAGCAGCUCAGAGCUCCUUCGGCAUUCCCUGCAGUGCAGUACCUAUCUCAGCCACAGCCACAGCCCUAUGCUGUGCAUGGCCACUUUCAGCCCACUCAGACAGGUUUCCUCCAGCCUGGUGGUGCCCUGUCCUUGCAAAAGCAGAUGGAACAUGCUAACCAGCAGACUGGCUUCUCCGACUCAUCCUCUCUGCGCCCCAUGCACCCCCAGGCUCUGCAUCCAGCCCCUGGACUCCUUGCUUCCCCCCAGCUCCCUGUGCAGAUGCAGCCAGCAGGAAAGUCGGGCUUUGCAGCUACCAGCCAACCUGGCCCUCGGCUCCCCUUCAUCCAACACAGCCAGAACCCGCGAUUCUACCACAAGUGACCAUCAGAUUAUAUCUUCAACACCACACCCCCCACCCCAUCGUGGGUGAGGGUAUCCCCUGUGUGUCCCAGGCCAAUAAAAUCUACCUGCCACUG